GAUUUUGUUUGUUUUCUCGUGAGCUUAGGCCGCUGGUUUUGGUGAUUUUUGUCUGAUUGCAAUGUCUGGACGUGGUAAGCAAGGAGGCAAAGCUCGCGCCAAAGCGAAAUCCCGCUCUUCUCGCGCUGGUCUCCAGUUCCCGGUGGGCCGAGUGCACCGCCUGCUCCGUAAAGGCAACUACGCAGAGCGGGUUGGGGCAGGCGCGCCGGUGUACCUGGCGGCGGUGUUAGAGUACCUGACCGCCGAGAUCCUGGAGCUGGCCGGCAACGCGGCUCGCGACAACAAGAAGACUCGCAUCAUCCCGCGCCACUUGCAGCUGGCCAUCCGCAACGACGAGGAGCUCAACAAACUGCUAGGCCGGGUGACCAUUGCUCAGGGCGGCGUCCUUCCUAACAUCCAGGCCGUGCUUCUGCCUAAGAAGACCGAGAGUCACCACAAGGCCAAGGGCAAGUGAUUUGACAGGUAUCUGAGCUCCCGGAAACGCUAUCAAACCCAAAGGCUCUUUUCAGAGCCCCCCUA